GCACACCUCUCGGUGCAGAUUGCAAAGCGCCUUCCGUUGCGAGAGCUGCAGAUUUUGCAAGAGCCAGGCUCGCCCACCUUGUAGAAGGAGCGCCUUGAGUCCCCUCUCACCCUCGGUUGCAAAGAGCCGACCGCUUGAUCUGGACACCCCCUCGCCCAGAUUGCAUGAUCUCCCGGGACCCUCUUGAGUUGCACGUUUCUGCACCGAGGACCUCAAAUCCCCGUCGCUCCUAGGAUUUGCAGCGUUCUGGAUACUGGAGGGUUGCAGGCUACACUCGCCCGCCCCUGGGCAGACACUCGUCCAAACCACUGGAGUGUGCUGGUGACUGGCAGGCCAGCCCUUCGCCUCUCCAUGAACCCGUGAGCCUGGGGGCAGGUGCCAGGCGAUGGCGCGGCCUGUGAGCGACAGGACCCCGGCCCCUCUGCUGCUGGGCGGCCCGGCCGGGACACCCCCUGGCGGGGGAGCGCUGCUUGGGUUGCGGAGCCUUCUGCAGGGGACCAGCAAGCCCAAAGAGCCGGCCAGCUGUCUCCUGAAGGAAAAGGAGCGCAAGGCGGCCCUGCCUGCAGCCACAACCCCUGGGCCAGGCCUGGAGACUGCGGGCCCGGCGGAUGCCCCGGCUGGGGCAGUGGUGGGCGGAGGGUCCCCGCGGGGGCGCCCGGGGCCGGUGCCCGCCCCGGGUCUGUUGGCGCCACUGCUGUGGGAGCGCACGCUGCCGUUCGGCGAUGUGGAGUACGUAGACCUGGACGCCUUCCUGCUGGAGCACGGGCUCCCGCCCAGCCCGCCGCCCCCCGGUGGCCCGUCGCCGGAGCCGUCGCCCGCGCGGACGCCCGCACCCUCCCCAGGGCCGGGUUCGUGCGGCUCGGCUUCCCCCCGCUCCUCUCCUGGGCACGCCCCCGCCCGGGCUGCCCUCGGGACCGCCAGCGGCCACCGCGCAGGCCUGACCUCUCGGGACACACCCAGCCCUGUGGACCCAGACACCGUGGAGGUGUUGAUGACCUUUGAACCCGACCCAGCUGAUCUUGCCCUAUCAAGCAUUCCUGGCCACGAGACCUUUGACCCUCGAAGACAUCGCUUCUCAGAAGAGGAACUUAAGCCCCAGCCAAUCAUGAAGAAGGCAAGAAAAAUCCAGGUGCCGGAGGAGCAGAAGGAUGAGAAAUACUGGAGCCGGCGGUACAAGAACAACGAGGCAGCCAAGCGGUCCCGUGACGCCCGGCGGCUCAAGGAGAACCAGAUAUCGGUGCGGGCGGCCUUCCUGGAGAAGGAGAACGCCCUGCUGCGGCAGGAAGUUGUGGCCGUGCGCCAGGAGCUGUCCCACUACCGCGCCGUGCUGUCCCGAUACCAGGCCCAGCACGGGGCCCUGUGAGGCUGCCCCACAUCCCCACCUGGCGGAGCUCUCCUCCGCCUUGCUGAGACUUACGCCCUGUUCCCUUCCUGCCCUGUGGCCCACGGGCCGGCCAGCUGGGUGCCCCAGGGACGUGAUAAUGCAGAUAAAUACAUUUAUAUUUUUAAGAAAAAGCGAGCCUCCCCCCUCCCUUGCGGGGGCGGGGAGGGUUCUCUGUGUGUGUCCCCGGCACGUCAGGGACCCUAUCCUCCCACCGCCUCCGUUAACACGAUCCUGAAUAAAUCUUGAGAACCCCAGAGCCAGCUGUUGUGGAAGAAGAGGGCAGCUCCCUGGCAUACUGGCUGCAGCCCGUGGGCAGCUCCGGGCUGUCGUCCAUAGAGGGCAGGCGCUGCUGGAAGUGCUGGAGUCUGAGUCCUCCCGCGGGCUGUCGGAUGGAGGAAGGGCAGAAGGUCUGAGAGGAAUGAAGCGACUGCCUUUAUUGCAUAGACCUUUUCAAUUGCUUUUUAGAUUGGGGACGGAGGACGCGCAUGAGACGAACAGGGGAUAUGAAUUUCCCCGCCCCCACCCGCGGGGAGAGGAACAUUAGUGCAAAUCCUAGCGCCGGCCCCGGGGAACCUGCCCCUCCUGGGCUGAUUGGCCAGCUAAAUGGAGGCACCGGAGUGGAUGGGGCGAGGCUGCGGGCCCUGACCGGCCGACUCACUGAGGCCUACCCCAGCCAGUACAUUCCAGGUCCUGUCAUUGGGCGACGCGUAAAAUAGACUCCGCCCUCAGCCAUCCUGGCCGGGUAGGAGCAGGUGGCAAGCGUCAGGACUGAGCCCUGCCCCGUAA